GUAGUUCUUCCUCUGCUCUGCUUCCCUUCGGAGGAAAAUUUCAGGCUGAAGGUUUAGCGGGUGCCGCCUCUAAAGAGAGCAAUCACUACACUUAUGGCUGGGAUUUUGCGCUUAGUAGUUCAAUGGCCCCCAGGCAGACUACAGACUGUGACAAAAGGUGUGGAGUCUCUUAUUUGUACAGAUUGGAUUCGUCACAAAUUCACCAGAUCAAGAAUUCCAGAAAAAGUGUUUCAGGCCUCACCUGAAGAUCAUGAAAAAUACGGUGGGGAUCCACAGAACCCUCAUAAACUGCAUAUUGUUACCAGAAUAAAAAGUACAAGAAGACGUCCAUAUUGGGAAAAAGAUAUAAUAAAGAUGCUUGGAUUAGAAAAAGCACAUACCCCUCAAGUUCACAAGAAUAUCCCUUCAGUGAAUGCAAAAUUGAAAGUAGUUAAGCAUUUGAUAAGAAUCAAGCCCUUGAAGUUGCCACAAGGACUUCCAGCAGAGGAGAACAUGUCUAACACGUGCCUCAAAAGCACUGGGGAGUUAGUAGUGCAGUGGCAUCUGAAACCUGUGGAGCAGAAAGCACAUGAGUCCUAAUGCCCCAGCAGCUUCCGAUUGGAAAAUGCAAAUUGUUUUUAUUUAAAGAUGGUGAGAAAGUGUUUUCAUUAAAAUAUGUUUUCAAAACCAUUUUCAGGCCGGGCACGGUGGCUCACCUGUAAUCCCAGCACUUUGGGAGGCCAAGGCGGGCAGAUCACCUGAGGUCAAGAGUUCGAGACCAGCCUGACCAACAUGGAGAAACCCCCAUCUCUACUGAAAAUACAGAAUUAGCCAGGCAUGGUGGCACAUGCCUGUAACCCAGCUACUCGGGAGGCUGAAGCAGGAGAAUCACUUGAACCCGGGAGGCAGAGGUUGCAGUGAGCUGAGAUGGUGCCACUGUACUCCAGCCUGGGUGAUAGGAUGAGACUCCAUCUCAGGGGAAAAAAAAAAAUUUUUUUUUCACUGACUAAACCUGCUGCAGCUCUCUUUUACUACAGACUUGGAGAUUUUAGUUUAAUUUGGUUUAAUUCUCUGUCCUUUCCCUUUCACUGUUUCACUCCAAAACAUGUAAGAAUGGCAAUGUUUGAACAUCUGCGUUUGGGUCUACUGCCACCUUAGCAAGCCUCAUUAACCAUUUUAUAAAAAUUGCGUUAGUAUUGUUGUUGUUGUUUUUGAGACAGGGUCUUGCUCUGUCACCCAAGCUGGAAUACAGUGGCAUGAUUUCAGUUCACUGCAGCCUCGACCUCCCAGGCUCAAGUGAUCCUCCCACCUCAGCCUCCAGAGUAGCUAGGACUACAGGCAGUGUGCCACCACAUCCAGCUAAUUUUUUAAAGUUUUUUCAUAGAGACAGGGACUCACUAUGUUGUCCAAGCUGGUCUCAAACUCCUGGGUUCAAGCCAUCCUCCCACCUCAGCCUCCCAAAAUGCUGGGAUUACAGGCAUGAGCCACUGUACCCAGCCAAAAUUGUUUUCUUUUUUAAGUGAAUUCAACAAUUUCUGUGAGUGGCUCUUUGCAUGAACACUGUGCAAGGUGUUGGAGAAAUCCAAAGCUGACCAAAACAUGGUCCCCACCUUUUGGAGCUUACAGUCUGUUCUGGGGAACAGAGAUUCAGCCAAAGUCAAGAAACACUGGAUGCCAGCUAGAUUAUCUGUUCUGUGCUUUGGUGUCUAUAAGUACAUAUGUGGAUAUGGGUUCAUUUUAUCCCUAAACUUAGUACCAAACCAGCAUUUAAUAUCUAAUUAUAAAUCUAAUUUGGCCUAAACUUUAUUAUUGCACACUGCCUGAACAAAACCUAUUUGUCUCUAUGUAAAUUUUUUCCUCAUGGAACAAGGGUGUGAAAUGAAAAUAUUUUAGGAUUUAUUCAAAAACAGACUAUUCUGUUUUCAGCUUCAGAAUUGUUCUUUGAAUCCUAAGGAACCUCUGUCAACAGUUGAGGUUGCUGUUGAAAAGAAAGAAGAAGGAGGCGGAAAUCUCUCAGGGAGAAUUAUUUCCUUUCUUUUCUAUUUUAGAUACCUGGAGGGGUGGGGAGAAGUAAGAAUUGUAAGGGAGGUUCAGUAGUGGGGAAUUCUGUGACAGCUGAUUGAAGAUGAUGAUGAAGAACCUCUGCAUUCUAGUUACCCUUUGCUUCCCUUCACCUCUUGUAAAAUUUGGCUUGGCAACAAUGACAUUGUCAUGCUUAUUGUCCCAAUAUCCAUCCUGUCGUAGAUCUUAAUGUUUUUGAUCGUUGCGUUAAAGUGGAAGUGCCACCCACAGUGAAACCAGAUCCCAUUAAUAAAUAAGCUUAAAGGCAACUGCAGUUUUAAUUCCAUAGUUAUUGAAUAUCCAGUGUGUGUAAGGCCUGGAGGGGAGCCAAAGGACACUAACUUCUAAGAGCUCCGUCUAGUUGGAGAGAAACCUGUGUGCCACAACAUACAGUGUCCUUGCUUAUGUGGGGUCGAAGACAUCUGUGAAAAUAAAAGCAGCCUCUGCUAAUUUAGCGCCAUCUCUUUUACUGUGCUAAUUUUUUUUUCUUUAGAGACAGGGUCUCACUCUGUCGCCCAGCCUGGAGGGCAGUGGUGUGAUCGUAGCUCACUAUUACCUCCAACUCUUGGGCUCAAGUGAUCCUCCCACCUCAGCCUCCUGAGCAGCUAGGACUACAGAUACAUGCCACCGCUCCCGGCUAGUAUUUUUUAAAAUUUUUUGUAGAGCCAAGUGUUGCUAUGUUGUCCACACUGAUCUGGAGCUUCUAAUCUCAAAUGAUUCUCCUGCCUCAGCCUCCCAAAGUGCUGGGAAUACAGGUGUGAGCCACCAUACCUGGCCUUACUGUACUAAUAUUAAUAUUGUGUAAAUAGGGGAAAAUACCAUGGUUAAUUUUUACUCAAACAGUAAGAAAGUUUGAGUAACUAAUUUUAAUCUCAACAGCCCAUAGCUAGAAGAGGGGAUCUAAAUGUUAAGUUGAAUAUUUAGAAAUAAAAGUGUCUACAAGAAGAAAAGUCUUUAGUGAAAAUAUGGGCAUAGGCCAGCAGCAUUAGCUUUCUAUUGCUGCAGAACAAAUUACCACAAACUUAGCUGCUUAAAACAACACACACUUAUUGUCUCACAAUGUUUGUGGGUCGGAAGUCUAGGCGUGGCUUAGCUGGGUAGUCUGUUUAGGAUCUCAGUGCUGGAAAAACGUGUCUGGCCAGGUGCUCAUUGUAGCUUUGACAGGGAAGGGAUCUGCUCCCAAGCACUCUCAGGUUGUUGGCAGAAUUUGUUUCCUUAUGGCUGUAGGAUUCAUGGCAAGUUGCUUCUUCCAAAACCAGCAUUGGAGACAGACUAGCAAGAUGGGCACUACACUCUUAGAUAAUCAAAUAAAUGCAAUCAUGUGCCUCGUGUCACCUUUUUUGCAUUCCAUUCAUUAAGAACAAGUUGCAGUUCCUACCUACACUCAAGGAAGGGAGGAAUUACACAGAAGUGUGACCACAGGAGGCAGGGCUCAUGGAGGCCUCCUUAAAGUCCCCCAGCCAAACCUGAAAAGUCAAUCCUGGACCUUAUCAUAGUGGCUGUAUAGUUUAGAAGGUUUCUUCAGAUUGGCAUUCCUUUGCCUCAUAUCAUCACUUCAAAACCCUAUAAGGGUUUGUUCCUCGGUCUUGACUUUGUGUCUUUGAGGAUUGCUUUGUUUAGUGUCACCUGCCUUCUUUCAGGAGGUUUUGCCUGACAUCUGGUGGUGACCGUGGCCACCAAGUCAACCCAAACACUACCUUUAAGGACGACUGCAGUUCUCUUAGGGUCUCCUCAAUCUAAAAUUGUACCUCUUUCAGGCCAAACACCUAUUUUCUUCAUUUUUUUUUUCUCAUAAGAAUGCUAGCUAGUAUGCCUAUUAUCUAACUGGCACAGUUUCACCAAGGACAGUUUGGAACUACACAGGCCAUUUUAGGGAGAUUUUGACAUGAACAAGAUUGCUUCUUUGGGAGGUACCUUAAAAUGAAAAGCAAAGAAACUUCCAUGCGGAGAUUGUCUUGUUUUUCUCAAAAUGGGAUAAUUUUGCUUAACAUAAGUAGUAUCCCUUCCUUCCUUUCCAUACUUUGAGAAUUAAUAAGGACUAGCUUUUUGAUCACACAGCUUGAUAAAAUUUUCAAGGGUCCAAAUUACUGUCUAAACCAUUUGCCACUCUUUGUGUAUAUUUGUCAAAAUCUGCUUUUCUAUAUCAAAACUUUUCUCUCAAGACCUGAGGGAAUUAAUUAAUAAGGAAUCCUUGGAACACUGGAAAUUCUAAAAUAAGAGUCAGAUACAAAACACUGGUCACUAAAAUUCUUACCUUUAUGUAUUAGAAUGGCAAUCAAUGAACAAACUGAAAAUGUCUUUGGAUAUUAUUUCUGUUUAUUUUUUGCCUCAAAAUUAUUAAAUGACAUGAAAUAAGUGCUCAAGAAGAAAAAUAAACAAUUCUUCAUUUCCUGUU